GUCAGAGUCGGCUCAGCCUGCGCCGGGGAACAUCGGCCGCCUCCAGCUCCCGGCGCGGCCCGGCCCGGCCCGGCUCGGCCGCCUCAGCAGACGCCGCCUGCCCUGCAGCCAUGAGGCCCCCGCAGUGUCUGCUGCACACGCCUUCCCUGGCUUCCCCACUCCUUCUCCUCCUCCUCUGGCUCCUGGGUGGAGGAGUGGGGGCUGAGGGCCGGGAGGAUGCAGAGCUGCUGGUGACGGUGCGUGGGGGCCGGCUGCGGGGCAUUCGCCUGAAGACCCCCGGGGGCCCUGUCUCUGCUUUCCUGGGCAUCCCCUUUGCGGAGCCACCCAUGGGACCCCGUCGCUUUCUGCCACCGGAGCCCAAGCAGCCUUGGUCAGGGGUGGUAGACGCUACAACCUUCCAGAGUGUCUGCUACCAAUAUGUGGACACCCUAUACCCAGGUUUUGAGGGCACCGAGAUGUGGAACCCCAACCGUGAGCUGAGCGAGGACUGCCUGUACCUCAACGUGUGGACACCAUACCCCCGGCCUACAUCCCCCACCCCUGUCCUCGUCUGGAUCUAUGGGGGUGGCUUCUACAGUGGGGCCUCCUCCUUGGACGUGUACGAUGGCCGCUUCUUGGUACAGGCCGAGAGGACUGUGCUGGUGUCCAUGAACUACCGGGUGGGAGCCUUUGGCUUCCUGGCCCUGCCGGGGAGCCGAGAGGCCCCGGGCAAUGUGGGUCUCCUGGAUCAGAGGCUGGCCCUGCAGUGGGUGCAGGAGAACGUGGCAGCCUUCGGGGGUGACCCGACAUCAGUGACGCUGUUUGGGGAGAGCGCGGGAGCCGCCUCGGUGGGCAUGCACCUGCUGUCCCCGCCCAGCCGGGGCCUGUUCCACAGGGCCGUGCUGCAGAGCGGUGCCCCCAAUGGACCCUGGGCCACGGUGGGCAUGGGAGAGGCCCGUCGCAGGGCCACGCAGCUGGCCCACCUUGUGGGCUGUCCUCCAGGCGGCACUGGUGGGAAUGACACAGAGCUGGUAGCCUGCCUUCGGACACGACCAGCGCAGGUCCUGGUGAACCACGAAUGGCACGUGCUGCCUCAAGAAAGCGUCUUCCGGUUCUCCUUCGUGCCUGUGGUAGAUGGAGACUUCCUCAGUGACACCCCAGAGGCCCUCAUCAACGCGGGAGACUUCCACGGCCUGCAGGUGCUGGUGGGUGUGGUGAAGGAUGAGGGCUCGUAUUUUCUGGUUUACGGGGCCCCAGGCUUCAGCAAAGACAACGAGUCUCUCAUCAGCCGGGCCGAGUUCCUGGCCGGGGUGCGGGUCGGGGUUCCCCAGGUAAGUGACCUGGCAGCCGAGGCUGUGGUCCUGCAUUACACAGACUGGCUGCAUCCCGAGGACCCGGCACGCCUGAGGGAGGCCCUGAGCGAUGUGGUGGGCGACCACAAUGUCGUGUGCCCCGUGGCCCAGCUGGCUGGGCGACUGGCUGCCCAGGGUGCCCGGGUCUACGCCUACGUCUUUGAACACCGUGCUUCCACGCUCUCCUGGCCCCUGUGGAUGGGGGUGCCCCACGGCUACGAGAUCGAGUUCAUCUUUGGGAUCCCCCUGGACCCCUCUCGAAACUACACGGCAGAGGAGAAAAUCUUCGCCCAGCGACUGAUGCGAUACUGGGCCAACUUUGCCCGCACAGGGGAUCCCAAUGAGCCCCGAGACCCCAAGGCCCCACAAUGGCCCCCGUACACGGCGGGGGCUCAGCAGUACGUUAGUCUGGACCUGCGGCCGCUGGAGGUGCGGCGGGGGCUGCGCGCCCAGGCCUGCGCCUUCUGGAACCGCUUCCUCCCCAAAUUGCUCAGCGCCACCGCCUCGGAGGCUCCCAGCACCUGCCCAGGCUUCACCCAUGGGGAGGCUGCUCCGAGGCCCGGCCUCCCCCUGCCCCUCCUCCUCCUCCACCAGCUUCUCCUCCUCUUCCUCUCCCACCUCCGGCGGCUGUGAACACGGCCUCUUCCCCUACGGCCACAGGGGCCCCUCCUCUAAUGAGUGGUCGGACCGUGGGGAAGGGCCCCACUCAGGGAUCUCAGACCUAGUGCUCCCUUCCUCCUCAAACCGAGAGACUCACACUGGACAGGGCAGGAGGAGGGGGCCGUGCCUCCCACCCUUCUCAGGGACCCCCACGCCUUUGUUGUUUGAAUGGAAAUGGAAAAGCCAGUAUUCUUUUAUAAAAUUAUCUUUUGGAACCUGAGCCUGACAUUGGGGGGAAGUGGGAGGCCCCGGACGGGGUAGCACCCCCCAUUGGGGCUAUAACGGUCAACCAUUUCUGUCUCUUCUUUUUCCCCCAACCUCCCCCUCCUGUCCCCUCUGUUCCCGUCUUCCGGUCAUUCUUUUCUCCUCCUCUCUCCUUCCUGCUGUCCUUCUCCGGCCCCGCCUCUGCCCUCAUCCUCCCUCUCGUCUUUCGCACAUUCUCCUGAUCCUCUUGCCACCGUCCCACGUGGUCGCCUGCAUUUCUCCGUGCGUCCUCCCUGCACUCAUACCCCCCCUUCAACCCGCCCAAAUGUCCGAUCCCCGACCUUCCUCGUGCCGUCCUCCCCUCCCGCCUCGCUGGGCGCCCUGGCCGCAGACACGCUCGACGAGGCGGAGCGCCAGUGGAAGGCCGAGUUCCACCGCUGGAGCUCCUACAUGGUGCACUGGAAGAACCAGUUCGACCACUACAGCAAGCAGGAUCGCUGCUCAGACCUGUGACCCCGGCGGGACCCCCAUGUCCUCCGCUCCGCCCGGCCCCCUAGCUGUAUAUACUAUUUAUUUCAGGGCUGGGCUAUAACACAGACGAGCCCCAGACUCUGCCCAUCCCCACCCCACCCCGACGUCCCCCGGGGCUCCCGGUCCUCUGCAUGUCUCAGGCUGAGCUCCCUCCCCCGCGGUGCCUUCGCCCCUCUGGGCUGCCAAUAAACUGUUACAGCCA